GGACCCCACCAUGGCUCACCGGCCCCCCAGCCCUGCCCUGGCGUCCGUGCUGCUGGCCUUGCUGCUGAGCGGUGCUGCCCGAGCUGCGGAGAUCGUGGGCGGGCACGAGGCGCAGCCACACUCCCGGCCCUACAUGGCCUCCCUGCAGAUGCGGGGGAACCCGGGCAGCCACUUCUGCGGAGGCACCUUGAUCCACCCCAGCUUCGUGCUGACGGCCGCGCACUGCCUGCGGGACAUACCCCAGCGCCUGGUGAACGUGGUGCUCGGAGCCCACAACGUGCGGACGCAGGAGCCCACCCAGCAGCACUUCUCGGUGGCUCAGGUGUUUCUGAACAACUACGACGCGGAGAACAAACUGAACGACGUUCUCCUCAUCCAGCUGAGCAGCCCAGCCAACCUCAGUGCCUCCGUCGCCACAGUCCAGCUGCCACAGCAGGACCAGCCAGUGCCCCACGGCACCCAGUGCCUGGCCAUGGGCUGGGGCCGCGUGGGUGCCCACGACCCCCCAGCCCAGGUCCUGCAGGAGCUCAAUGUCACCGUGGUCACCUUCUUCUGCCGGCCACAUAACAUUUGCACUUUCGUCCCUCGCCGCAAGGCCGGCAUCUGCUUCGGAGACUCAGGUGGCCCCUGAUGGGUGACUGGCCGUCCCUGUCCUCCAGGGAGACUCAGGUGGCCCCCUGAUCUGUGAUGGCAUCAUCCAAGGAAUAGACUCCUUCGUGAUCUGGGGAUGUGCCACCCGCCUUUUCCCUGACUUCUUCACGCGGGUAGCCCUCUACGUGGACUGGAUCCGUUCCACGCUGCGCCGUGUGGAGGCCAAGGGCCGCCCCUGAACCGCCCCUCCCACAGCGCUGGCCGGGACCCCGAGCCUGGCUCCAAACCCUCGAGGCGGAUCUUUGGACAGAAGCAGCUCUUCCCCGAACACUGUGGCGUCCGGGACGGCCCCACCCGUCCCCCCACACUCCCUCCCACGGGGCUCCGGGAGACAGGCCGGCCCUGCACCUCACCCCACCGUGACCUCAAUAAACGUUGAAACUCC